GCGAGACUCCAUCUCAAAAAAUAAAAAGUAAAAUAAUAAAAAAAAGUAGUAUAGGCAGCAUCAAAAUUACUUGUAAAGCAGUGUUUGUUAAGGCUUUGUACUCCUCACUUAUGCAUUGUAUAAUAUUUAAUUUGCCUUUGGAAAAGUGAAUAUGGUGAUAGUUUAUCCUAGAAGUUGUUUGUGCUGAUGUUUUGGCAUUUUCAAGAAAAACACAAAUAUGUAAAAUGUAAUCAAGUGUCAAAGGGAAACUGACAAAUGGCUCUUUGAUCUCAAGUAAAUAACAGCUUCUAAAUACAGAUGUAUAUGUCAAUAGCCUGAAUUUUCUUGAAUAUGUUUCUGUUUUGACUCCUUUUGUAGAUUGAUUUGUUCCACAGCAACCACCAGGUAGAAAUAUUCUAAAGGGCAAGAAAGAAAAGGGAUAUAUUUGGUGUGGAGAUUUUUUUUUUCUUUUUUUUUUUUUUUAGAGACAAAGUCUCACUCUGUUGCCCAGGCUGGAGUGCAGUGGCUUGAUCUCGGCUCACUGCAGCCUCCGCCUCCCGGGUUCAAGCACUUCUCCUGUCUGUCUCAGCCUCCCGAGUAGCUGGGACUACAGGUGCAAGCCACCAUGCCCGGCUAAUUUUUGUAUUUUUAGUAGAGAUGGGGUUUCACUGUGUUGGCUAGGAUGGUCCUGACUCGUGAUCCACCCACCUUGGCCUCUCAAAGUGCUGGGAUUACAGGCGUGAGCCACCCCACCUGGUGUGGAGAUUUUAAGUGACUUUUGAGUCAGAGCAGUGAGCUUUUUUCCUUUUCAUUCUAGUAAUUAUUUAAGAAUGUUUAAAAUGUAUUUUUGUCAUUAUAUUUUAAGUACACUAAUAAAUUUUUUCUGAAUUGUAUGCUUCUGUUUUUUAAUUGCGUGAAUAGCUUGAAUUUCCUCUCCUGAAACAACCUCAAAUUCAGUUUGUCAAAGUCAGAACACAUAAACUUCUUCCUCAAUGGGUUCUGUCAAUCUAACAGUUUAGCAGAGGUGAUUAUAUAGCUCAGUUCCAGGCAUAUAAAUAGAUUAUGAGAAUAAGAUCCUGGAAACUGUUUUUCACUGAACCCAGCUGCUGCUGUAUUAGGUCUGCAAUAAACUGAAAAUGACAUUUUCCAUAUAUGCAGGUGAAUCAAGAACAUAAACAUUCUAAGAGUGUUUUACAUCUUUCACACACCCCUUUCAUCACUUUAACUGGAUUAGUAGGUGGUAGCUUGGGCCAAUAGUUUACCACCUCAUGCAGAGCUGACUUGAUUUCCAAACAUUUUAUUGUCUCUUUUGGAAAGUAGGUUAAUACACGUGACCCAAGAGGACCCAGAGCAAGAAACAAGCACUCAAUGGACAAGUCAUAUGAAGCAGGGUAAGAGCACUUACCAUCAUACUCAUACCCAUGGGCCUACAACUGCUCUUUCAAGUAGAUGGUGAUGAUAAGGCAGCUAUUAAUUGAGAAUUGACUUGAAGCAGCUUUGCUCAGAUCUUUGCACAUAUUAUCUCAUUUAUUAAUCUCAGGAUAAUCCUACAUUAGUUACACUUAUAACCCCCUUUUUAUAAAUGAGCAAGCUGAAACACAGAGAGGGCAAGUCACUUGUUCGAGGUCACAUAUUAAAUGGCAGAUUCAAAAUAAGAACUCAGACUUUCUGAAUACAGAGCUGCAUCUACUACACUCUCCUGCCUCUCAUUUUGGCAAUAAAGUUUUUGGCAGAUGGUGAUCACAGAAGUUGCUUAAAGUCACAACUUUUAAGUACUCUUUUUUCUAAAGUCAAAUUGUAUAGUUUUUAUCCUAAAAAAUUAUAUUAUCACUUUUGUAGUUUAGAAGAGGAAGGUGUGAAAAUUUGAAAUGUUAUCUAUUCUCAUUUAAUUUCCUACUUUCCGUGGAGAGUAUUCCAUACCCAGAUUAAAUGUCAUUUCCAAUUGUUGCUCACACUUACCAAAGGGAAGGUCUCUGCUCAGUUUUGAGCAGAGGCUCCCUGUGUAGGAGUAUGACAGUCCUCAGUAAAGUUUUGUCACCUAUGUUUGGCAAAACAUCCUGGGCAGAUGAGCGAUUCAUGUGGCAAGAGCACUGCCAAUUGAAAAGGUGCAUUAGUAUGAAUAUUAGCACCUCUAAGUGUUUGUGAAAUAGCAAAGGUAGAAGGACUAGAAUAUUGACAAAGCAUUUUCAAAAAAUUAUACUACUUCUAAUAGCUUAACAUGUUGAUAGAAAAGACGAUUCAGUGUAGAAGUCUGUGAUGAUUCAAUUCUAAGUUGUAUGUAAUAGAGCUAAAGUCUGUAAUUAUAUUUUAGAGGAGUAUUAAACAAUAUAAACAUGAUCUCUGAGUCAUAAAUGUCAUUAUUACACUGAGUUUUAAAUAUAAUUCAUUUAUAACCAUAUAAUAGACACAUAAUAUUACUGUGUGACAAGAAAUACUCUUAGAUGUAGCAAGAAAAAAUGGAAAUUACAAACAUAUGUGAUUUCAAAAUAAUUCUUAACAUUUCUUCAGGGGUUAUUACAAAGCAAAUGAAAGGAAUUUUUACAAGGUGUAGUUCAGUUGCAGUUUCCCUCCUCUGUAUUCACAUUAUUGCCACAGCUUACGAAUGACAAACAUUUGUGGACUAUGGCAGCAAUCUGUUGGGUGUUUCAAUCUAUUUUGAGCUGAAAUUGAUUAGCACUUUAUGAAAAGUGUACAGAAAAUUACCAUGCUUAUCAAGGCAAAUCAAGCCAUAAUUCUGCCUUUUUUUUUCUACACCUGCAGCUAUGAAUAUUUUUUGGUGGGUACAUUGAGACGUGCUCAAGAAUAUACAUAUUGGACUGCAUAUCAUGCAAUUUAUUCUGAUCUUACUGACAGUUUGCAAACAAAAACUCAAAACAAGAUGCAACUGUGUGCAGCUCCUGAACUGUAGGUUCUGAUUUUGGCAUCCAUGAAUGCACGAGGAAAGGGGGUGCAGCUGAAGAGGUGUGCUUUUGCUCAUCUUACAGUGAAAUAUAAUCUGGGCAUUUGUUUGAUGGAUUUCAUGAAAUAUGGAGGAAAUCUGAACCAAGGGUUUCACCUGAUUGCUUUUAUUUGCCCCACCUCGGUAAUAAUAAUAAGUGAAAAUCAGCUGGAGUUGAUGACUGUGGAGCCAUAAGUUAACCAUAUUGAAGGAGAAUCAUUAAGAAUGAGGAAAGGAGAAAGUGGGCAAUGAUGGUGAUCUUCCUUUUUUGAGAAGAAGAUACCCACCUCUCGCCAGUCACCCCCUGCCAUGGCAAUCUUUCAAAGAAAAGCAAAUAUUGUAGGCCAAAAUAAAAAGAGGAAGAACAUGGACUACAUUGGGCUCCUUGUUUGAGUGGGUGUUUAAUGUAGAAAAAUGGUGUAGAAAUAGGUUAGUUUUUAUGCUGUCGCUCUGGGCAGACUUGAGAAUAAAUAUAAUGAGAUUAAAAAAGACUGGGGGACCAUAGCAUAGUGCUUGGCACACAGUAAAGUCCCCAAGAAAUAUUUGCUGUUUGAUUUUUAAAUAUAUUUAUACUUUUAUCUAAUUCUCUUGUGGUGUCAAAUUCUUUAUAACUAACAGCUUUACAAAAAGUACUAUGUAUUCUUUUCUGUAUGACCUUAUUUAUGAGAUUCCUGUUCAUUUUUGGUUACUGAGAUUUACUGAACAAGGUGAUGUUCAGCAUAGGCAAAUAUUUCUUUCUUUCUUCUUUUUUUUUUUUUCUUUUUGAGAUGGAGUUUCGCUCUUGUCCAGACUGGGGUACAAUGGUGCGAUCUCUGCUUGCUGCAACCUCCCCAUCCCAGGUUCAAGCAAUUCUCCUGCCUCCUCUUGAGUAGUUGGGAUUACAGGCACGUGGCACCAUGCCCAACUAAUUUUUGUAUUUUUAGUACAGAUAGGGUUUCACCAUGUUGGCCAGGCUGGUCUCAAACUCCUAAUCUCAGGUGAUCCAUCCUCCUCGGCCUCCCAAAGUGCUGGGAUUACAGGCAUGAGCCACCACACCCAGCCUCUUCUUCUUUUUUAAAGUAAGAGCUGGAUCUAGUUUGUUUUCAGCCUUCAUCUUUGUAUGCUUGAUGUUUGUUUGCACACACCAAAUCCAAGUGUAGGAUUCUAGAAUUUAGGAUUAUGUUUUGCUUUGAUUUUCAUAAUGGUACUAGUGGCUAAUAACUUCAGAGAACAUUCCUCAGUGACUUUUGAGUUCUUUUUUUGCUAUUAUUUCUGAUAGCUAUGAGCACAUUUUACUAGAGAUAUAAAUUAUAUGAUUUCUCCCUAAGUGUAUUUGCCUUGCACUUGUGUCCGUAUCGAUUGGCCUCAGUAAGUAGAAUGCAUGUUUCCAUAGGAACUAGAAUAAUAACUUGAUAUUACUGUGCCUAGUGUUUCAUUGUUCCAUGAAAACAUUUGCAAAGCAAAAGAAUGUGAAUUUAUAUGCUAAUAAUCUAUCAAUUUUUGCUUUUUAAAAAUGUGUCUUUUUGAAAAGCUGCACUUUACUCCAAGUAAACCUAUUUCUCUUCUUCAUUAUUUUUGAGGAAAAAUUGUUAGUAGUAAUUAUUGGAUUUUUCACCUCUCAUUCCUCUAUUAUAUAAGUUUAUGAAAACUAAAUGAAAAAAAUGCAGUGAAGGUAAGAUUCAGUGCCAAAUCUCUCCAAGUGUAUGUACCUCCAUACGCUUCAUACAGACUUCUUUACAGCAUAAGGCUACUAUUUAUUUUUAUUGUUCUUGAAAUCAGUGUAUAGGUUGGGUUUAAUUUUAUUGACACUCCUUUUUAAAACAAUUCAGACUGAUUUCAGAAGAGACAUCUUUUGCAUCAGAGAGGACUAAACUAUGCAAAGUGGCAUCUUUUGAAGAAUGCUUAUUACCAGAGUGGUAGCAAGGAAUUUUGCUCAAGCAGUUCCUAUAGUGAUUGCAAACUGGCUCACUUCCCAGCUCUUAACAAUUUCAGCGUGGGUUUUUCUUGAUUGACCAUCAGUCAUCAGCAUCUCUGAACAUAUACAUUACACACACACAUACACACUCACAACAUACACAUAAACACACUUGGCCAGACAUAAGGUAAACAAACAAAAGACUGUUAUUGAAGUCGAGGAACAGCUUACGCAGAGCAAUUUAAUCUUUUUGCAUAAAUAAGAUCCCUAUUCUGUUAAGCUGUUUUGGAAUAUGGAAAGCCUAUAAAUGCUGACUUUUAAUUUUGAGAAAUCAGAAUCAACUGUAGAAUGCUUUCUAGUGGUUCAAAUAUUCAGGGUCUAUGACUAAUCCCACCCUGUUUCCUUCAUAGAUUCUUUAUAGUUUAAAACACAGACUAAGUAUUCUAAAACUAAUUUGUAACUGCCUCUUCCAAAUUUCUGGGUUGUUGGCUCAUUUAUUCAUUAACUCCAUCAUCUACUUUUGGGACAUUUCCUAUAUGCCAGGCUCUGCACUAAGCAGAGUGUCAGAAACCUUCCUGCAGAUACCCCCUGGCUCAUUCUGCCUCUGUACCACUCCUUCAUGGCACAGCCAUGGGCAUCUUUUAGCAACACAGAUUUGAUCACAUGACCGUCCUGCUUAAAACUUUUCAAGGAAGUCCCAUUACCAUUUUCCUAAAUUUCAGAGUCUUUGUCAUAGCUCACAGAGUCUUGUGUGAUGUGGCCCCUGCCACCCUCUCAAACCUCAUUUCAUUGUAUUUCAUCCUUUACCCAUUGAAUUCCAGCAACACUGGCCACCUUUCUGUGCACAGAUGAGGCCAGGAUCUUUCUCAGUUGAGCCUUUGCACGGUGAGCUUUUGCUGUUCCUCUUGCUAGGAUAUUCUAUUCCCUGUUCUUUUCAAAGUUUCUUCCCUUUCUUCAUGUCUUAUCUUGUGACAUUUAAAUGUCACUCCUUGAAGAUUCUUUCCCCAACCACUAUGUAAAUGGGCCUUCCCUGCAACUCUCUUUUGUUACAUUGUUUUUCUUAUAGUACAUUAACAGUUCUAAACAUACAUUUAUUUGCUUUGUUAUUUUCUGUCUCCCCCACUACAGAAUGAUGUUGGGAAGGAAUUUAUAGACAGUGCCAAAAUUAUGAGAUUGAAGCUUCUAUCCAAUUGAGGAGCAGGUAUAGUGGGAAUGAGCAGUUGAGAGAGCCAGAAAGAUAAAAGAUUGCAGCCAGAUGACAUUAGAAAAUUAUAAGUGUCCAGCAGUUCUUAGAACAAUUUUGGGGGUGAGACUAUGGGUGUAAGAGGCCAAUGUCAAGUGGAGGGGAAGUGAGGAUUGUUAGAUUUGAGUGUCCACCAUGUGUGAGGCUUCAUUAGGCACUUGGUAUAUAAGUCUCAGUUCAUGCCUUCAAGUGCUCCAGACUUGUCUAUAAAACAAAAUCCGGUGCUCACAAGCUGCCACAAUACUUUUAUCAUUCUAACUUGAUUCUCCAAUGAUGCCAUUUAGUAACCUCCUACCUCUGCCACAUUCUUCUUUGUAAAUCCUGUUUAGAUCUGCUCUAUGCCUUUCCUUUUUCUCUGUCUAAAUCCCAUCCAUCCUGUAAGCAUCAACUCCUGGAAGUCAUUUCUAAUCACCUCUUUCUGCACUGCCCCCAUCCCCUGUUGUGUCAUCUGUCUCUCCCCUAAACAUGCAGAGUUGUGUCUGCCUCCUUUUGUCUGUGCUUUCACUGUAUUUUAUUCUUUGUCUCACAGAUCUUAUUUUCCCAACUAGACUUAAACACCUUGAGUGUGUAAUAGUUUCUCAUAUGUCUUUGUAAUAUGUCUCAAUAAAAUAUCUUAGGAAAGACAUGGGGAAAAUAUUUGAUCAUGGAAGAUUAAGGAGAAUUUUUCUCAUGUAUAGCUGCUAAAUAAAAACCAACUACAUAGUAUAGAAUGGUAUAUGAUGCUAAUACGUAGCCAAUUAAGAAAUUAACCAUUUGACUGCUUUGUAUAUAAAAUGAUUGUAGUGCCUGUUAUUUCAGUAAGAAGCUGAUGGAGAGGGAUAUGUUAGAUGUUUAAAUGGCAUAGUUAAGGUAUUCAAGGUUAAACCUUUUUUUUUUUUGGUCUGAAAUAUCAGCAAUAUAGCUUCUAAAUUUUUAUGGCUGCUUUUCUGUAUCACUUUAUCUUAUGUGAAAUUUCAGAAUGAUUUAUCUGUAAUAAACAUCAUCAUCUGACAUGGCUGAAAACAGUACUUUUUGUUCAUUUUGAUUUUUGGAUAAUGCAAAAUUAUAGAUUUUUUAAAAAUUAUAUUCAAAGAAUACUGAGUGCAAGACAAUCUUUCUAGGUUAAAAAAUAUCUUAUAAACCUGAAUUGUCAAUUAUUAUUGUAUCCCAGAUGUAUGGAAGUUAAUGGAUAGUCAGUAACAUACAGGACUAGCAGAAGGUUUGUUGUUAUAGGUAAUCUGGAGAGAAGCCAGGUAAGUGGAAUUUGGGAUUUGCUGCUGUUGCCAGAAAGCAGCACAGAGACAUGGUAAGUGGCAAGACCCAGGUAACUAAAACAACCAUGUCUUAGUCCUUUUAUGCUGCUGUAACAGAAUAUCACAGACUGAGUAAUUUAUAAUGAACAGAACUUUAUUUGUCUUCUGGUUCUGGAGACUGGGAAAUCUAAGAGCGUGGCAUUGACAUAUGGUGAGGGCAUUUGUGCCUCAUCAUCCCAUGACAGAAGAUGGAAAUGCAAGAGAGCUCAAAAGCAAGAGAGCAAAUGGGGCCAAACUUGCUUUUUAUAACAAGCCACUCUUGUGAUAAUGAACCAACUCAAACAAUAAAGACAUAAAUCCAUUCAUGAGGGCAGAGCCCUCAAGGAUGAAUCACUUCACUUCUUAAUGGCCUCAGCUUCUAAUACCAUCACAAUAGUAAUUCAGUUUCAACAUGGGUUUUAUAGGGACGUUGGAACCACAGCAAACUGUAACCAUUUUGAUUUCCUUAUUUGCACCAUUUUAAAAAAACCUAUUUAUUUAACGGCUGUUUAUUCAGUGCCUAUUCUGUUGUGUUGGAGACUAGAGGUAAUUACAAAGGGAAUAAGACAAACAGUCACCCACUCUGGUGAUGCUUCCCUUAUCUUCAUAAUGCAUUUGAUCCUGUGAUUCUUUGGCACAUGAGUCCAUUGCAUCUUGCAUAUUAGUGUCCAGUAAGUUUUUCCUGACCAAUUGAUAAUAUAGAUAUACAUUGGUAGCAGUUUUGUGUAUAUUUUUAUAGUUAGAUGUUGUUGGCACAUGUGACUUGUGUCUCAGAAAAAUACAGAAAAUGGUUAAAGACAGGAGGAUACUACCCUGAUUUCUCUGUUCAUUAAAGAACAGCUAUUUGGGGGGAAAACCUGAUACAAUUAUUUGAGCAUGUGGCUUAAAGAUUAGACCUAUAAACAAUUCAGGAGCAUCUUCCAGCAAACUGUGUGAGAAUUCACAGAAAUAAACCUGGUAGGUUUGUGCUAUGUUAUUCACAUGGGCUGUUAACUCUUUUCCAUUCCUAGGUCCUUUAUUUCCCUGCCCUCCUCAAUCUCAUGCUCUUGAGAUUUUUAACUAUAUUACUUCUUUACAAAGUCAUCUUCAAAAUGAUUCAUUUUGGAUAGCAAACUAUCCCUCAACUUACCUACACACUCUCACUCAUACUCACAUUCUCUCUUAUGUCUUUCUGUGUGGAAGGGAACAUUUAGAAUGUCUAUUCUUUGUGAUGCAAAAAUGACAACACACUGAUGAUGAAGGGGGGUAUUUUUAGGAGAAAAAGUAGCUUUUCUUUUCAUCAUACUGCCACUUUUGAGAUUCUAUAGAAAGAAUAGGUAUUGAACACAGACCACUUGGCUCUCUGAGGUAUGCUUUGGACACACUUAGAAGUCAGCUAGAAUAUGCCUUCUGUUUAAGGUUGGAGUCUGCAUUUAAAAAGAGAGAACUGGAUUAAUUGGCAGUUCCCUGAAUGUGGUUUCUACGGAAUGUAUGAUAAGAUCCUGCUUUUUCGCCAUGACCCUACCUCUGAAAACAUCCUUCAGCUGGUGAAAGCGGCCAGUGAUAUCCAGGAAGGCGAUCUUAUUGAAGUGGUCUUGUCAGCUUCCGCCACCUUUGAAGACUUUCAGAUUCGUCCCCACGCUCUCUUUGUUCAUUCAUACAGAGCUCCAGCUUUCUGUGAUCACUGUGGAGAAAUGCUGUGGGGGCUGGUACGUCAAGGUCUUAAAUGUGAAGGGUGUGGUCUGAAUUACCAUAAGAGAUGUGCAUUUAAAAUACCCAACAAUUGCAGCGGUGUGAGGCGGAGAAGGCUCUCAAACGUUUCCCUCACUGGGGUCAGCACCAUCCGCACAUCAUCUGCUGAACUCUCUACAAGUGCCCCUGAUGAGCCCCUUCUGUCUCCUGUGAGUCCUGGCUUUGAGCAAAAAUCACCAUCAGAGUCGUUUAUUGGUCGAGAGAAGAGGUCAAAUUCUCAAUCAUACAUUGGACGACCAAUUCACCUUGACAAGAUUUUGAUGUCUAAAGUUAAAGUGCCGCACACAUUUGUCAUCCACUCCUACACCCGGCCCACAGUGUGCCAGUACUGCAAGAAGCUUCUGAAGGGGCUUUUCAGGCAGGGCUUGCAGUGCAAAGAUUGCAGAUUCAACUGCCAUAAACGUUGUGCACCGAAAGUACCAAACAACUGCCUUGGCGAAGUGACCAUUAAUGGAGAUUUGCUUAGCCCUGGGGCAGAGUCUGAUGUGGUCAUGGAAGAAGGGAGUGAUGACAAUGAUAGUGAAAGGAACAGUGGGCUCAUGGAUGAUAUGGAAGAAGCAAUGGUCCAAGAUGCAGAGAUGGCAAUGGCAGAGUGCCAGAACGACAGUGGCGAGAUGCAAGAUCCAGACCCAGACCACGAGGACGCCAACAGAACCAUCAGUCCAUCAACAAGCAACAAUAUCCCACUCAUGAGGGUAGUGCAGUCUGUCAAACACACGAAGAGGAAAAGCAGCACAGUCAUGAAAGAAGGAUGGAUGGUCCACUACACCAGCAAGGACACGCUGCGGAAACGGCACUAUUGGAGAUUGGAUAGCAAAUGUAUUACCCUCUUUCAGAAUGACACAGGAAGCAGGUACUACAAGGAAAUUCCUUUAUCUGAAAUUUUGUCUCUGGAACCAGUAAAAACUUCAGCUUUAAUUCCUAAUGGGGCCAAUCCUCAUUGUUUCGAAAUCACUACGGCAAAUGUAGUGUAUUAUGUGGGAGAAAAUGUGGUCAAUCCUUCCAGCCCAUCACCAAAUAACAGUGUUCUCACCAGUGGCGUUGGUGCAGAUGUGGCCAGGAUGUGGGAGAUAGCCAUCCAGCAUGCCCUUAUGCCCGUCAUUCCCAAGGGCUCCUCCGUGGGUACAGGAACCAACUUGCACAGAGAUAUCUCUGUGAGUAUUUCAGUAUCAAAUUGCCAGAUUCAAGAAAAUGUGGACAUCAGCACAGUAUAUCAGAUUUUUCCUGAUGAAGUACUGGGUUCUGGACAGUUUGGAAUUGUUUAUGGAGGAAAACAUCGUAAAACAGGAAGAGAUGUAGCUAUUAAAAUCAUUGACAAAUUACGAUUUCCAACAAAACAAGAAAGCCAGCUUCGUAAUGAGGUUGCAAUUCUACAGAACCUUCAUCACCCUGGUGUUGUAAAUUUGGAGUGUAUGUUUGAGACGCCUGAAAGAGUGUUUGUUGUUAUGGAAAAACUCCAUGGAGACAUGCUGGAAAUGAUCUUGUCAAGUGAAAAGGGCAGGUUGCCAGAGCACAUAACGAAGUUUUUAAUUACUCAGAUACUCGUGGCUUUGCGGCACCUUCAUUUUAAAAAUAUCGUUCACUGUGACCUCAAACCAGAAAAUGUGUUGCUAGCCUCAGCUGAUCCUUUUCCUCAGGUGAAACUUUGUGAUUUUGGUUUUGCCCGGAUCAUUGGAGAGAAGUCUUUCCGGAGGUCAGUGGUGGGUACCCCCGCUUACCUGGCUCCUGAGGUCCUAAGGAACAAGGGCUACAAUCGCUCUCUAGACAUGUGGUCUGUUGGGGUCAUCAUCUAUGUAAGCCUAAGCGGCACAUUCCCAUUUAAUGAAGAUGAAGACAUACACGACCAAAUUCAGAAUGCAGCUUUCAUGUAUCCACCAAAUCCCUGGAAGGAAAUAUCUCAUGAAGCCAUUGAUCUUAUCAACAAUUUGCUGCAAGUAAAAAUGAGAAAGCGCUACAGUGUGGAUAAGACCUUGAGCCACCCUUGGCUACAGGACUAUCAGACCUGGUUAGAUUUGCGAGAGCUGGAAUGCAAAAUCGGGGAGCGCUACAUCACCCAUGAAAGUGAUGACCUGAGGUGGGAGAAGUAUGCAGGCGAGCAGGGGCUGCAGUACCCCACACACCUGAUCAAUCCAAGUGCUAGCCACAGUGACACUCCUGAGACUGAAGAAACAGAAAUGAAAGCCCUCGGUGAGCGUGUCAGCAUCCUCUGAGUUCCAUCUCCUAUAAUCUGUCAAAACACUGUGGAACUAAUAAAUACAUACGGUCAGGUUUAACAUUUGCCUUGCAGAACUGCCAUUAUUUUCUGUCAGAUGAGAACAAAGCUGUUAAACUGUUAGCACUGUUGAUGUAUCUGAGUUGCCAAGACAAAUCAACAGAAGCAUUUGUAUUUUGUGUGACCAACUGUGUUGUAUUAACAAAAGUUCCCUGAAACACGAAACUUGUUAUUGUGAAUGAUUCAUGUUAUAUUUAAUGCAUUAAACCUGUCUCCACUGUGCCUUUGCAAAUCAGUGUUUUUCUUACUGGAGCUUCAUUUUGGUAAGAGACAGAAUGUAUCUGUGAAGUAGUUCUGUUUGGUGUGUCCCAUUGGUGUUGUCAUUGUAAACAAACUCUUGAAGAGUCGAUUAUUUCCAGUGUUCUAUGAACAACUCCAAAACCCAUGUGGGAAAAAAAUGAAUGAGGAGGGUAGGGAAUAAAAUCCUAAGACACAAAUGCAUGAACAAGUUUUAAUGUAUAGUUUUGAAUCCUUUGCCUGCCUGGUGUGCCUCAGUAUAUUUAAACUCAAGACAAUGCACCUAGCUGUGCAAGACCUAGUGCUCUUAAGCCUAAAUGCCUUAGAAAUGUAAACUGCCAUAUAUAACAGAUACAUUUCCCUCUUUCUUAUAAUACUCUGUUGUACUAUGGAAAAUCAGCUGCUCAGCAACCUUUCACCUUUGUGUAUUUUUCAAUAAUAAAAAAUAUUCUUGUCAAAA